GCAAAAGUUCCGGGCGCCCGAGCCGGCUGCUCGUGCCAUGGAGCGGAGUCCCGACGUGUCCCCCGGGCCUUCCCGCUCCUUCAAGGAGGAGUUGCUCUGCGCCGUCUGCUACGACCCCUUCCGCGACGCAGUCACUCUGCGCUGCGGCCACAACUUCUGCCGCGGGUGCGUGAGCCGCUGCUGGGAGGUGCAGGUGUCGCCCACCUGCCCAGUGUGCAAAGACCGCGCGUCACCCGCCGACCUGCGCACCAACCACACCCUCAACAACCUGGUGGAGAAGCUGCUGCGCGAGGAGGCCGAGGGCGCGCGCUGGACCAGCUACCGCUUCUCGCGUGUCUGCCGCCUGCACCGCGGACAGCUCAGCCUCUUCUGCCUCGAGGACAAGGAGCUGCUGUGCUGCUCCUGCCAGGCCGACCCCCGACACCAGGGGCACCGCGUGCAGCCGGUGAAGGACACUGCCCACGACUUUCGGGCCAAGUGCAGGAACAUGGAGCAUGCACUGCGGGAGAAGGCCAAGGCCUUCUGGGCCAUGCGGCGCUCCUAUGAGGCCAUCGCCAAGCACAAUCAGGUGGAGGCUGCAUGGCUGGAAGGCCGGAUCCGGCAGGAGUUUGAUAAGCUUCGCGAGUUCUUGAGAGUGGAGGAGCAGGCCAUUCUGGAUGCCAUGGCCGAGGAGACAAGGCAGAAGCAACUUCUGGCCGACGAGAAGAUGAAGCAGCUCACAGAGGAGACGGAGGUGCUGGCACAUGAGAUCGAGCGGCUGCAGAUGGAGAUGAAGGAGGACGACGUUUCUUUUCUCAUGAAACACAAGAGCCGAAAACGCCGACUCUUCUGCACCAUGGAGCCAGAGCCAGUCCAGCCCGGCAUGCUUAUCGAUGUCUGCAAGUACCUGGGCUCCCUGCAGUACCGCGUCUGGAAGAAGAUGCUUGCAUCUGUGGAAUCUGUACCCUUCAGCUUUGACCCCAACACCGCAGCUGGCUGGCUCUCCGUGUCUGACGACCUCACCAGCGUCACCAACCAUGGCUACCGCGUGCAGGUGGAGAACCCGGAACGCUUCUCCUCGGCGCCCUGCCUGCUGGGCUCCCGUGUCUUCUCACAGGGCUCGCACGCCUGGGAGGUGGCCCUUGGGGGGCUGCAGAGCUGGAGGGUGGGCGUGGUACGUGUGCGCCAGGACUCGGGCGCUGAGGGCCACUCACACAGCUGCUACCACGACACACGCUCGGGCUUCUGGUAUGUCUGCCGCACGCAGGGCGUGGAGGGGGACCACUGCGUGACCUCGGACCCAGCCACGUCGCCCCUGGUCCUGGCCAUCCCACGCCGCCUGCGUGUGGAGCUGGAGUGUGAGGAGGGCGAGCUGUCUUUCUAUGACGCGGAGCGCCACUGCCACCUGUACACCUUCCACGCCCGCUUUGGGGAGGUUCGCCCCUACUUCUACCUGGGGGGUGCACGGGGCGCCGGGCCUCCAGAGCCUUUGCGCAUCUGCCCCUUGCACAUCAGUGUCAAGGAAGAACUGGAUGGCUGAGCUGGCCCGGGGCUGCCCCGGUCUUGUGCCACAGCACUGUUUUCUUUCUGCCCUCUUCCUAAUGCCCACACUGCUUGGGCACUAUUGCGCCCCUGCCUCCUUGCCAGGCUCUUCCUCCUGUCCUGCCUGGUCCUUUUCCAUGACUCCAGGCUGUGCCUCUCUCCAUGUUUGGUCCCUUCUGUGCCCAUGGUCAGGAGCUAUUCGGGUGGCACCUCGCUGGCCAGGCUCUCCCGAGUCGUGGCACCUCCACAAUGUGAAUUUUCUGAAUCCCUAUUCCAGGAUUUCUGGGAAUAAUGUUUACUUCUAGAAUGGGCCUGUUGUAAACCAUCUCAUCGAGGUGUGGUAAAGCCAUUGGAUGAGGAGGGGACUGCCAUGGAAAGGAGAGUUUGUUACUUACGGUUCUGAGAGGAGGGGCCACAUAGGAAAGCCCCACGGUGGGUCAGAAGGCGGAAGGAGGGAGGGGAACGUGUGGGCAAGAGACUUCCUCUGGUUUCCUCAGGAGGAAAUGGGCAAGGCAGAGUAAGCAGGGGAGACAGGUUUAAGGGUAGCUGGCUUGAGUAAUUUCAGUGGCUCUCAGGAUAGGGGCUGCCCUUUUUGUCUGAUACCUGGCCCCGGGAUAGUCAGGACAGGUGAAUGUUGGCCUGGGGUGUGACAGCCCUGGGAGAGCCAUGUGAAGGAGGCAGCUGGCGCCAUCGCUCCGGAUUAGUUGGUUUCCAUAGGAAAGGCAUGCUUUCAGCCAGAUGCUUGCCAUCUCUAGGGAUUGGGGGAUUGGCUAGCCUGGGAGGAUCAGUCUGUCCAGGUCAGCGAGGCCCCAGAUACCAGAGCAUCAAGAGUACAGGAAAUACAGUUAAUGCAGGGCCUCUGUGUGGCUGGAUCCUCCGUCUCCAUCAGAUCAGCUCUGAUUGAUCUAUUCUUGCACGAUUUCCUCUGAACACAGGGUUCCAGAGUACUUAAACACAACAUUUUUUAAAUCGUGAUUUCGGCCUAUUUCCUUGCCAGGCCUGUUUCCCCACCAGGAAAUGAGAUAGGAGGACUGGAUGAGGAUGUCCUGUUAUAGUUGCUGUGGAGGAAGUUCCUCUGGUUAAUUCUCAUCAGCGUCUGCAGAAAAGAAGGAAAGAGGGCACCCUUUUCAGUUGGGAAGAAAGGAGAGGGGUGGCGCCAUGGACGUGGCCCUAAACGCUGUGGGAGAGGGAAGAGGAGGCUGGGCCUCGCUGCCCUCUUGUCUCUGCUGACUUCAGCCUGGUCAUGCUUGCUCUGCCACUUGCGAUUUCAUCCCUAAUUUCUUCCUCCACCAUGCCUGCAGACUUUUCCCUGGGCUUGUUUUUUCUCGCACAUCUCUGAAGAGUUUUUAAUCUUCAGCUCAUCAUGUCCCAGGAAGUGGCAUCAUAAAAGGAAAUAUUUUUUUUUCCUAGGAGCAGUGUUAAAAUCUGGGUCACAUUCCUGACCAAGGACAGCAUCCUGCCUUCUGCCCAUCCCCUUCAGUUCACAAAAGCUGACAUUUUAAACAAAUCAUGACUCACACGUAUUAAUUGGUUAUAAAUAUGUUGUGUACACUGGUUAGAUAAAACUUAAGGCCACAAGGAGGGCCCAGGUAGGCGAUGUCAGUGUGUGAAGGGGCUGGAUUGGGCGUGGUGAGGAUGUUGGCAAACCAGUGCAUGCACCUGGUUGGAAGAUGCUCAGCCUCACAAAAGCUCCAAGCCCUUUGGGAGCCAAAGUGUCUGAGAGUGUGACCCUCUCCUGUAAAGUAUUUAUCCCACCCAUUAAUAUAAUUUCUGUAUAAUAAACUUGACCUGAAAUUAUUUCAUUCUUUAUAUUAAACUUUUAAAAAUGUUUUUUAUUUUCACCUUAGAUAUGGGAAGAGUUUUUUUUUUUUUUUUUUUUUUAACAGGAUAACUUGAGCAGGCUAGGCCUCUUAAAAAAAAAUUUGAGCUAAAACUCAUUUUUCUUUUGGCAUUUUCUUUUCAAUGUUCUUAUAAGCAAAGUUCAUCCAUGUUGUAGCAUGUGUUCAACUUUAUUUUUUCAUCGGGUAAUAUUCCAUUGUAUGGAAUGGUAGUACUACAUUUUAUUUAUCAUGCAUCGAUUGGUGGACAUUUGGAUCGUUUCUACUUCUUGACUAUUAUACAUAAUGCUGCUAGGAACUUUUGUGUAUGAGUUUUUGUGUGGACAUAUGUUUUCAUUUCUCUUUGGUAUAUGCCUGGGAGCAGAUUUGCUGGAUCAUAUGAAACUCUAUUUAACCCUUGAGGGACUCCCAAACUGUUUUCCAAUGUGGUGACACAAUUUUAUAUCCCAUCAACAGGGCAUGAGGGUUCUGAUGACUCCACAUCCCUCAGUGCUUUUUAUUAUCUAUCUUUUAACUUAGCCAUCCUAGUAGGGGUAAUGUGGCAUCUCAUUGUGAUUUUGGUUUGCAUUUCCCUGAUGGCGAAUGAUAUUGAGCAUCUUUUCAUGAGCUUAUUGGCCAUUUGCAUAUCUUCUUAGGACAGCUAUCUUUAGAUCACUUGCUCAUUUUUUAAUUGGGUUAUUUGUCUUUUUAUUAUUGAGUUGUAAGAGUCCUUUUAUAGCCUGGCACAAGUCCCUUUAACUGGUAUAUGAUUAUAAAAUUUUUCUCCGUGAGCUGUUUCAUUUCCUUGAUGAUGUCCUUUGAAAUACUAAAGCUUUUAAUUUUGA